UCAAGCGAUGCUCCUGCCUUCAUCUCCUGAGUAGCUGGGACUACAGGCACACCCCACACUGUUAGCCUGAGACAGCUAUAGGGAAAGGUCGCAGGAAGAGUGUUGGGCUCAGACACCCAAGAGGCCUCUUUUUUUCCAGGAAGCCACUCACCAAUCAACAUCCAGACUCCACAUUGGGCCCAGGUCUCAGUGGUCAUCUGCAUCAUCAGGUAAACAUGUGCAGAGAUGCUGACCAGAGGAGAACAGGCAACAGGGGGACCUGCAGGCAAAGCGUUAACCUUCUUAUCCCUGGACCUGAACCCAGGCGCACAUCUGGAUUAGAAGAUGCCAGGCUCAGAGGAUCUUCGUAAAGGCAAGGACCAGAUGCAUUCACACAGGAAACGAACCAUGUUCACUAAGAAGCAACUGGAAGAUCUGAACAUCUUGUUCAAUGAGAACCCAUACCCAAACCCCAGCCUUCAGAAAGAAAUGGCCUCGAAAAUAGACAUACACCCAACAGUACUGCAGGUCUGGUUCAAGAAUCACAGAGCAAAACUCAAGAAAGCGAAAUGCAAGCAUAUUCAUCAAAAACAAGAAACUCCACAACCGCCAAUACCAGAGGGUGGGGUCUCCACCAGUGUCGGCCUGAGAAAUGCAGACACACUACCCAGAUUGCCCAACGCUGCUCACCCGAUCGGCCUGGUGUACACGGGUCAUCGAGUCCCCUCAUUCCAGCUCAUCCUGUACCCCAACCUCAAGGUCCCUGCAAAUGACUUCAUUGGCCACAGAAUAGUCCAUUUUGGCUGCUGCCGAGAUCCUAAUAUAUACUGCCUCUACCCCAUUUUGGAAUCCCAAGUUUGCGCUCCAAGCUUCCAUUCUGGCUCUCCUGCCUGUUCAUCUAACCAAAGUCGAGAGAGAUGAUAAAUACAAAAAGUCACAUGUUGUAA